AGAGACGCAAAGUUUCUGCUCCGGGAGGAGGCGGCGGCGCCGCGGGCUCGUCGCCUGGGGGAGCAGAAGCGGGUGGGAGGUGCGGGUGGCCUUGGCCUCAGCCCUGGUGCGCGGGGGCCGGGGGUGGUGACCCUCCUGGCCGAGGAGGGGCGGCGUCCAGACGCCCGCUCGGGGGCCGCCUUCCCCCCCACGCCUGCCCCCGGGCACGCGCCCUGCCCGGUCCCUCGCCCCGCGCCACUUCCAGUCCGCAGAGAGAUGCCCUCCACGUUUCUGCUUUCUCUGCAGCCUCUAGAUUGCCAGAUGCGACUGUGCGCCUCGCUGGGUGUGUUUUCCACAGCCCCUUCCUCCUCGGCGUGCAGGGCUGACAUCACCGACUGCGUUUCUGGUUUGGCGGGUGGGGAGAUGGUUCCCCGCAGGGUUCUGGUACACCUUUGCCCCCAGGGCUAGCGCCAUUUGGGGGAGGAGGUUUUCGUUGUCGAGAAAGUUGGAUGCUCCUGGUAACCCCUCUAACAAGAGAGUUCUGUAGCGAGGUGGGACUGUUCUCCCCAUAAGGUGACAGUUUCUCUUGCGAGGUGUGGCAGCGCUUCCUGUUGUACAAGACAGAUGUUGCCUUGGCGUUACGUAAAUCAUCGUGUCUCCGUCAUUUAAAGAAAGCCAAUUUUUAGUGAUUGAGGUAGAAAGAAAGAUCCGUUUAUAAUUUGUAAAAACAAAUUUUCACCCAGAAUCAAUAUAUUGGAACACCAUUCCUACUGUUAAAGUUUUCACUUAAGAGUAUAAACUUCAUCAGCUUUCUAUUAGGACUUAUUUUGUAAUUGGCUUCUUAGGCAUCCUUCUUUAAAAGAGAAAUCCACGUUAGCUCUCCUUGAGGUCUCGAGUUCCCUCGGCUGGAGGCACAGGUUCAGUGGAGACCAAAUAAUGCAGGCUGAUCAGCUGACCGAAGAACAGAUUGCUGAAUUCAAGGAAGCCUUCUCCCUAUUUGAUAAAGAUGGCGAUGGCACCAUCACAACAAAGGAACUUGGAACUGUCAUGAGGUCACUGGGUCAGAACCCAACAGAAGCUGAAUUGCAGGAUAUGAUCAAUGAAGUGGAUGCUGAUGGUAAUGGCACCAUUGACUUCCCCGAAUUUUUGACUAUGAUGGCUAGAAAAAUGAAAGAUACAGAUAGUGAAGAAGAAAUCCGUGAGGCAUUCCGAGUCUUUGACAAGGAUGGCAAUGGUUAUAUCAGUGCAGCAGAACUACGUCACGUCAUGACAAACUUAGGAGAAAAACUAACAGAUGAAGAAGUAGAUGAAAUGAUCAGAGAAGCAGAUAUUGAUGGAGACGGACAAGUCAACUAUGAAGAAUUCGUACAGAUGAUGACUGCAAAAUGAAGACCUACUUUCAACUCCUUUUUCCCCCCUCUAGAAGAAUCAAAUUGAAUCUUUUACUUACCUCUUGCAAAAAAAAGAAAAAAGAAAAAAGUUCAUUUAUUCAUUCUGUUUCUAUAUAGCAAAACUGAAUGUCAAAAGUACCUUCUGUCCACACACACAAAAUCUGCAUGUAUUGGUUGGUGGUCCUGUCCCCUAAAGAUCAAGCUACACAUCAGUUUUACAAUAUAAAUACUUGUACUACCUUAAUGAUAAGGACUCCUUAAAGUUCCAUUUGCUAAUGAUUAAUACACUGUUUGGGCUGGCCAGUUUUUCAUGCAUGCAGCUUGACGAUUGAGCACAGUCAGGCCUUUGUAUUAAAAAUGAAAAAUGAAAAAACAAAUUCAAAACCUAUUCAAAUGGGUUCUAGUUCAAUUUGUUUAGUAUAAAUUGUCAUAGCUGGUUUACUGAAAACAAACACAUUUAAAAUUGGUUUACCUCAGGAUGACGUGCAGAAAAAUGGGUGAAGGAUAAACCGUUGAGACGUGGCCCCACUGGUAGGAUGGUCCUCUUGUACUUCGUGUGCUCCGACCCAUGGUGACGAUGACACACCCUGGUGGCAUGCCCGUGUAUGUUGGUUUAGCGUUGUCUGCAUUGUUCUAGAGUGAAACAGGUGUCAGGCUGUCACUGUUCACACAAAUUUUUAAUAAGAAACAUUUACCAAGGGAGCAUCUUUGGACUCUCUGUUUUUAAAACCUUCUGAACCAUGACUUGGAGCCGGCAGAGUAGGCUGUGGCUGUGGACUUCAGCACAACCAUCAACAUUGCUGUUCAAAGAAAUUACAGUUUACGUCCAUUCCAAGUUGUAAAUGCUAGUCUUUUUUUUUUUUUUUCCAAUAAAAAGACCAUUAACUUAAAGUGGUGUUAAAUGCUUUGUAAAGCUGAGAUCUAAAUGGGGACAAGGCAGGUGGAGGGGAGGCCAGUGUACAUGUAAAUGCCCACAGCCCAGCAUUGGGUUUCCCUCCCAAGGCCCCAGCACCAACCUCUGAGCCCAAGACCUUGCCUGAAAACAAGCAGAUACCGAUUGCUUCAUCCUAUUUAUGGACAUGUAGGUCUAGUUGCAUUUUCACUGGGGGGAGGGGGGAAGGUGAAUUAUGGUAACUUUUAAUGAUCUAUUCAGGCAGUAGAGCUCUUAAGGAAAAAAAAAAACCCACUUUCUCUCAAGCAUGUAUUUAGGGGUUGUUCUCAAUUGUGCUGCUGAUUACCUGUCUUAUGUAACUACUUGAGACCAUCUGCAAGAGACAUGAUUUAGUGUGUCUGUAAUUCAAUCUUCGCUGUGUGUGGUAGAAGCAGUAGUCACUUUUGUAAGCCAGUCUCUUCAUGCCUAAAAGACACUACCAGUCACCUUUGAUUCGCGACUUUUAAUUUAUGAUUAUACUUAGCCUCCUCCUCCUUUUUUUUUUUUUCCCAAGUUGACUUGACUUUGCUUUUUUCCCCCCAAGUAGAACUAAUGCUAGCUUCCAGCUUGAAAGUAAAACUCCAGUGUGGAGUGAAUUUUGUGUCUAAUUAUAAACCUGUAACCAAAACUCAGACAUCUGGUACUGGUCUUUGCAUUGAGAUUGGUCCCUGUAAAACCCCCUUUAAAAGCAUAUUGCAUUUAGUACAGAGCUCUUUUUUGAAAUGAAGGCUGGAGAUGUGCAUUUUUCACGGUGUUAACUGGUUGUAUCUUAUUAGCAAGGAGAUUGGGGUUUUGAGUGUUUGCGUGGGUGGUUUCAAUUUGCCAGGGAACAGUGGCAGGCUGCUAGCAAGGCAGUGAGAAGCUCUUGGCAGCCAAAUGGGUGCAUUCAGGGCUGAUUUAUAGAGACCCUUGGCUUCUCCUUCUCCUACUCCCUGUCUUUCUGGCAUUUUGUAGCUUGUUAGAUUUUCUGCCAGAGGGGUGGGUCAGAGCAGUGGAGGGGAGACAUCGCCCAUGUGCUUCUGCUACUGGUCCUUGGGCUGGGUGGUUGGUAGAGGAGAUGUUGACACUAUGAGCUAAGGGUUGGCUUUUGUAAUUACCUGAAUCUGAAAGGAAUGCCUAAGGUUACCUUGGGGUUUCUCUUCUGGUGAGAUAGGGUUCCUGGUUUGAGUAAGUUAAUGUCCUGGAUAUUUCUUGUGGCAGGGGGUGGUCAAAGAGCCUGAUUGCUGACCCAGUCUCAGGCCUGUGGUCGAUGACCUCUCGGUAGUUUCAAAGGGGGCUGGAGGGGGAUAUUUGACUUGUUUUUUCGAAAUGUAGCCUUCUAACCCUCAAGUCUUUAGAAGCUGGGUGGACUCUUAGUGGUCCUGCAGCGUAUCCUAAAAGACUACCUUUGAAACAGGAUUCUUGUAUGGCCAGGAUCCUGUCUGGGAACCAGAAACCCUACACCCUCCCCCUCCAGGGAAUGCUGAGUUCCAGUUUUGAGCAGAGGUGAGGCAGAAUCCACUGUAGCCUUCCGCCCUGGUAUUUGGGGGGAUGACCAGCCCAGGCGUUGGGUGUUAGUCUGCAUGAGUUUGUGAGAGGAAAUAGCUGGGUGUCCUGGCAGUGCCCUUGAAGUUGGUUAGGACCUUCCUGUAAACUCUUGCCCCUACUUCUAACUACUCUAUAAAUAUAUACAUAUAUUUAUAUAUAAAGUGAUUAGUUGAACUGGCAUCCUGCUUUAGCCUGAGACUUGCCAUAAGAAACUGCUGAGUACUUGGCAAACCCUUUCAUAGUUUUGUUCUCCAUCUGUUUGGGGUAGGUGUUGAGCGAGGCAAAUGGAUCUCGAUAUUUCAGAUGGGCUUUUGAUGCACUGUUGCCAAGGAAGGCUUUUUCUGAUUUUUUGACAAAUGAAUUUUUGCACACUUUCAUUGGUGUCUUUCGGCAACUUACACACAUUGAAAAUGAGCUAUUGUACAUAUUUUUAUAUUCUCUUUAUAAAUGCAUGUCUGAUUGUACUUGUAACAAUAUUGUAAUGAACGGCUGUGCAGUAGGCCCAGCGCUGCUGUGUCUCGUCAGAGGAAUAGCUUACCACGAACCCCUCAGCAUACUGGGAAUCUCUUCCUGAACAACGAAUGUAAAUUUGGUCAAGUCUACUCUUCCGUUCAUUCAAUUAUUUUAAGCAUUUGAAUUAUUUAUUGUAUAUCCUAAAUAUAUUUCUCCUUUGGCAGUGACUAGAUUUCCACUAAUGUGUCUUAAUCUAUCCCUCCAGCUGGCAGUUACUGUUUUUUUAAUCCCCUGAAGUUGUCCUGUAGGAGACAGAAAUUCUUUGCUGUCUGUAUCCCUUGGAGUAAGAAGGUAGUGGCAUGGGUGGAGUGUGUGUUCUUUCUCCAAAUCUAUUAUGAUGUUUAUUAAACACUUCUGUAGCAAAGAUGGUGGUAGUUCUUUUGUUACUGAAGUUGCCCUUCACCAUGGCUAUUUGAAAAGGAGAUGUACUUGGACGUUUCUGUAAAUCUUGAGAUAAACUGUUUGGAGAUUUAACCACCUCUCUGAUGGGGGACCAACUCUAUGGAAAUUGUAAAUACGUUUUAUUUAUAAACCUGGCACUGUAUUCAAUAAACAUUUCUGCAGCCUUUCAUCUCUAA